CAAACGCCUGGCGCCCUCCGUCGCCCGGUUUCCAUGGUGACGGGGCGCCAGGCUAGGGCGGCCUGGCCACUGAGCCGGGGUGCAGUGGCAGCGGGAGAGUACCUGGCGAUGGCGAUAUGAGCGGUGCGGGGGUGGCGGCUGGGACGCGGCCCCCCAGCUCGCCGACCCCGGGCUCUCGGCGCCGGCGCCAGCGCCCCUCUGUGGGCGUCCAGUCCUUGAGGCCGCAGAGCCCGCAGCUCAGGCAGAGCGACCCGCAGAAACGGAACCUGGACCUGGAGAAGAGCCUACAGUUCCUGCAGCAGCAGCACUCGGAGAUGCUGGCCAAGCUCCAUGAGGAGAUCGAGCAUCUGAAGCGGGAAAACAAGGGUGAGCCGGCGCGGGGCCCUAGGCCGGCCCUGCCUCCCCAGGCACACUCAACACUGCCGCUCCCGCAGCACAGAAACACAGCCAUCAACUCCAGCACACGCCUGGGCUCAGGGGGAACACAGGACGGGUCAGACACACCUCUGUUAAAAACUUUAUAGAGGGGCCCGGGCGCGGCGGCUCACGCCUGUAAUUCCAGCACUUUGGGAGACCGAGACGGGCGGAUCGCGAGGUCAGGAGAUCGAGACCAUCCUGGCUAACACGAUCUCCGUUACAAGCUCAUAAUGAAUCAGACAUCACAGAAGAAAGAUGGCCCCUCAGGAAACCACCUUUCCAGGGCCUCUGCUCCCUUGGGCGCUCGCUGGGUCUGCAUCAACGGAGUGUGGGUAGAGCCGGGAGGACCCAGCCCUGCCAGGCUGAAGGAGGGCUCCUCACGGACACACAGGCCAGGAGGCAAGCAUGGGCGUCUUGCGGGCGGUAGCGCCGACACUGUGCGCUCUCCUGCAGACAGCCUCUCCACGUCAAGCUUCCAGUCUGUCAAGUCCAUCUCUAAUUCAGCCAACUCUCAAGGCAAGGCCAGGCCCCAGCCCGGCUCCUUCAACAAGCAAGAUUCAAAAGCUGACGUCCCCCAGAAGGCGGACCUGGAAGAGGAGCCCCUACUUCACAACAGCAAGCUGGACAAGGUUCCUGGGGUACAAGGGCAGGCCAGAAAGGAGAAAGCAGAGGCCUCUAACGCAGGAGCUGCCUGUAUGGGGAACAGCCAGCACCAGGGCAGGCAGAUGGGGGCGGCGGCACACCCCCCAAUGAUCCUGCCCCUUCCCCUGCGAAAGCCCACCACACUUAGGCAGUGCGAAGUGCUCAUCCGCGAGCUGUGGAAUACCAACCUCCUGCAGACCCAAGAGCUGCAGCACCUCAAGUCCCUCCUGGAAGGGAGCCAGAGGCCCCAGGCAGUCCCGGAGGAAGCUAGCUUUCCCAGGGACCAAGAAGCCACGCAUUUCCCCAAGGUCUCCACCAAGAGCCUCUCCAAGAAAUGCCUGCUUCUGAGCCCACCUGUGGCGGAGCGUGCCAUCCUGCCCGCACUGAAGCAGACCCCGAAGAACAACUUUGCCGAGAGGCAGAAGAGGCUGCAGGCAAUGCAGAAACGGCGCCUGCAUCGCUCGGUGCUUUGAGCUACCCGCAUCUGGUCAGUGCCAGGCCCACCAACCUGCAGCUGGAGAUUGGCUCUCUAUAGCAUUUCCUGACACUUCCGCUACUUUUAGGCCUGGCUAAAUUCCAAGAUAGAUAACACUCAAGAUAGAUAAAGUACUUGAUCUCCAAACUGACAAACUGUUUAUUUUCUAGCUGUUAUUUUGCUAUUUGGCAUUUACAUAAAAGCACACGAUGAAGCAGGUAUCGCCUUACCUGUUGAAACUGAAAAUAAAGCUUGUUUAUUUCCAA